ACCUACCUCGCCGCGGCCGCACAGAUUCCCCGCCUGAUACCGUCCCAGGAUCCCAGGGGAAACCUGACGGCCAGGUUCCCUCGUGCCAGCUGCCGGGAGGCGGGAGGGAGUGCCCUGAAACUCUAAUCUCAUUGCCUGGCCAGAAAAGGAAGUAAUCCCUAGUGUCAGCAGAUUCAGCGGUACUGGUGUAUAAUAGGAUCACCAAUAUACAACAGGAAAAAACAAAAGUGAAAGAUUAUCAAUAUAGAUUAUUGAGUAGGAGUAAAGAAGGUAAAUCAAAAAGGGGAAAAGAGAUUACAGACACAGAAAAUGUCAGACAACAAAGAAAGGAAGAGUCAAGGAUUUCCUAAAGAAGAUAACCAAGACACAAGUUCAUUAGCUGAUGCUGUAGAGAAAGUUGCAAAGCAACAACAAUCACAAGCAUCAGAGAUAGAAAAAAACAAAAAGGUUCUGUUCAAUUUGAAGAAUGAACUUCAUGAGCUUGAAAAAGAAAUAGCAGCUAUCUCUGCAGAAACUAAAGAAACAGAAAGACAAAUUUAUCAACAAGAUUCUGCCAUAGAGAAUACCAAACUUCAUUGUGAUAGCCUGGAAACUCAAAUCAAAUCCUUACAUUCAGAAAAUGUAAAGCUUAAAUUUGACAUAGAAACAGCCCAAGAAGAUUUUGAGGAACACAUGAUAAAAUAUAAUGCAUAUUAUGCAAAAAUAAAAGCACAUAAAAAUAGUUUGGGGGAAGUAGAGAGCAAAUGGUCAUUUAUGACUGAACUCCAUGAAAAGCGAGAUUUUGUUAAAAAAUUAAAGACAAUGAAAGAAGAACUUAUGCAAGAUCUUCAAAAUCCAGGAGGGAACCGAAUAACACAAGUACAGGAAGACAUUACAAACUUAAAGGAUAAAAUUAUAACUGUAAAAGAAUCUAUCAUUGAAAAAACUUGUUUUCUUGAGGAAGAAAAAAAGACACAUGAAAAAUUAAGAAAAGAAAUAGAGGCAAAGCGAGAUGACCCAAUAGAAGCCUGCACCACUCAUUCCCCAAGCAGGAGCAUCAAAUUCUAACUAUACUCAAGAGCACCAUCAUCACAAGAACCCAAAUCAGGUGAGCAAUCACAGUACCUAGUUUCAACUCCAUAUUUCUGAAAGAGGCUAGAAGAGAUAGUCUUGAAGAGCCAAACUACCACUCCUCCAUACCCCAGCAGUGACUGGGGGCUCAGAGAGAGAAUCUGUGCACUUGAGGGAGGGACAACUGGGGGACUUUACACUGAACUCAGUGCUGCCCUGGGAGUAGAGAAUAAAGCUGUGCUGGGCUCACCUAGCGCCCACGCAUGGAGGAGGCUUUCAGAGCAGACCUAGCCAGAGGGGAUUCACCCAUCCCAGUGAUGGAAACUUGAGUUUCUCUGAAGGCCUUGCCACUGUGGGCCAUAAGUGCUCUGAUGUCCUAGGUAAACUUGAAGAGUAAUCUAGGGCACAAGGAUUGCAAUUCCUAGGCAACGCCUAGUGCUGGGCUGGCCUUAGAUCCUGGGAACUUGUCAGGUAAAUGGCCUAGAGCAAUACCAGACAGCGAGGCCAAGGGAGUGCUCGCACAACUCCUGCCUCAACCCCAGGCAGUGCAGCUCACAGAGAUGAAAGUGACUUCUUCCUUCUGCUUGAGGAAAGGAGAGCAAAGAGUAAAGAGGACGUUGUCUUGAAUCUUGGAUACCAGCCCAGCCACAGUGAGACAGGACAUCAGGCAGAGUCAUGAGGCCCCUCUUUCCAAGCCCUAGCUAGUGGAUUACAUUUCUAGACACACCCUGGGCCAGAAUGAAACCUGCUGCCUUGAAGGGAAGGACCCAGUCCUGGUAGGAUUCAUCACCUGCUGACUAAGGAGUCCUUAGGCCCUGGAUAACAAACAGCAGUACCCAGGUAGUACACCAUGGGCCUUGGGCUCUGAGAUGUGUUGGCUUUAGGUGUGAUUUAGGACAUUCUCAGCUGUGGUGACUACAGCAAAAGACUCCUUCUGUUUGAGAAAAGCAGAGAGAGAAGUAAAGGGGACUUUGUCUUGCACCUUAGGCACCGGCUUGGCCACUGGGGAGUAGAGCACCAGCAGACCCUUGGGGUCCCCGGUUCCAGGCCUAGGCUCUUGGAUGGCCAUUUCUGGACCUGCCUUAUAAAAGAAGGGGAGCCCACCACUCUGAAGGGUGAGUCUCAGGCCUGGAAGCAUUCAUCACAAGCUGACUGAAGAGCCCUUAGGCUCUAAGUGAACAUCAGCAGUGCCCUGGCAGAACCCCACCAUGGGCUGGUGGUGGUGGCAGCCACAGGGAGAGGCUCCUCUCUCUGUGAAAAGGAGGGAGAAGAGUGGGAAAGGCUUUGUAUUGUGGUUUGAGUGCCAGCUUAGCCACAGUAGAAUAGAACAUCAGGUAAAUUUCUAAGGUUUUUGACUCUAAUCCCUGGCUCCCAGACAGCAUCUUUGGACCCAACUGGGGCCUGGGGGAACUUACCACCCUUAAAGAAGGGACACAAACUUGGCUGGCUUCGCCACCUGCUAAUCAUAGAGCCCUAGGGCCUUGAGUGAUCAUAGGCGGUAGCCAGGUAGUGAUUACAGGGGGCCUUGGGUGAAACCCAGUGCUGUGCUGUUUUCAAGUCUGAAUUGGUGCAGUCCCAGUGGUGGUAGCCUGUGUUCCCCACCCCCAGUUUCAGGGAACUCAGCAGACAGAGACAGACUCCAUUUGCGGGAAAGUGAGGGAAAAGAACACGAGUCUCUGCUUGGUAAUCCAGAGAAUUCUUCCAGAUCGUAUGCAAGACUGCCAAGGCAGUAUCUCUAUGAGUCUGCAAGAACCACAGCAUUAUUGGGCUUGGGGCUCAAGUUCCUUCUAACACCUGGAAAGCCUUCCCAAGAAGGAGGGGCACAAACCAGCCCAGACUGCAAAGACAACAAUAAAUGCCUAACUCUUCAGUGACCAGACACUGACGAACAUCUACGAGCAUCAAGACCAUCCAGGAAAACUUGAGCUCACCAAAGAAACUAAAUAAGGCACCAGGGACCAAUCCUGGAGAAACAGAGAUAUGUGUCCUUUCAGACAGAAAACUCAAAAUAGCUGUGUUGAGGAAACUUAUGAGAAAUUCAAGAUAACACAGAGAGGGAAUUCAGAAUUCUAUCAGAUGAAUUUAACAAGGAGAUUGAAAUUAUUUAAAAGAAUCAAGAAGAAAUUCUAGAGUUGAAAAAUGCAAGUGACACACUGAAGAAUGCAUCAGAGCCUCUUAAUAUCAGAAUUUAGGCAGAAGAAAUAAUUCGUGAGCUUGAAGAUGAGGUAUUUGAAAAUACACAGUCAGAGGAGACAAAAGAAAAAAGAAUAAGAAAGAAUGAAGAACACUUAAAAGAUCUACAAAAUAGCCUCAAAAGGGCAAAUCUAAGAGUUAUUGGCCUUAAAAAGAAGGUAAAGAGAUGGGGUAGAGAGUUUAUUCAAAGGGAUAAGAGCAGAGAACUUAUCAAAUCUAGAGAAAGGGCCAGGCCUAGUGGCUUACGCCUAUAAUUCCAGCACUUUGGAAGGCUGAGCCAGGCAGAUCACUUGAGGUCAGGAGUUCAAGACCAGCCUGGCCAACAUGUUGAAACCCCAUCUUUACUAAAAAUACAAAAAUUACCUAGACAUUGUGGCAGACGCCUGUAAUCCCAGCUACUCGGGAGGCUGAGGCAGGAGAACAGCUUAAACUUGGGAGGUGGAGGUUGCAGUGAGCCAAGAUUGUGCCACUGCACUCCAGUCUGCACUACAAGAACAAAACUCUGUCUCAGAAAAUAAAAAUGUUUUAAAAACCCCUACAUAAAGAUAUCAAUACUCAAGUCCAAGAAGGAUAUUGAGCAGCGAGUAGAUUUAACCCAAAGAAGACUAUCUCAAGGAAUUUAAUAAUCAAACUCCGAAACUCCCAAAGGUCAAGGAUAAAGAAAAAAAUCCUAAAACACAUUUUUCUUACUGGCUUAUCCUGGACCUUAUGGAAUAGCAUAUGGAAUAAGACAUUUGAGAAUAAAAUUUGGUUUAGGAUAGCACUAUUAUAAGUUGAUAUCAAACAUUGUUCUAAAUAGAAAAAUACUUUUCAAGAAUAUUCUCAAUAGCAUGUGUGUUUUCUCUACAGCAAUUUUUAAAAGAACGCAUACCCUUCAAAAUGUGUAAUUAUAAAAGCUAACGUGUACUGGACCUUUACUGUGAGCCACAGCAACACUAUAAAGUGGAUCACAAAUAUUCUCAUUUUAGAGAUGAGAAACUGAUUUAUUUCCCGUGAUUCUUAUAUGAAGAAAAAUUCUGCUUCAUCAGCUCUUUGAUUAACUGGAAACAUGGUUCAUAGAAGAGAGGCAGGAUUGAUACUCGAUUCUUUCAUUUUAGUUUUCAAUUUUUAGAAUAAGAAGCCAGUGUUCUAGCCAUAUUCAAAGGUAAUAAGCCAGAUUCCCUUUUCAAAGCAUUAUAAUUAACUCGUAGAUUUUUAUAUAUUUGAUGUUGUAAUCAGUGACAGUAUUAUUAUUGAUGUUCAAAUAGCCCUAUCUUUGACCAGUGAGAGCUUCUCAAGUUACCUUUAAUGUCCUUUCGGCAAAACCCCAAGUUUUUGUAACUUACUUGCUUAAGGAGUGUCAAGUUGUCUCAUACUUACCAUCUAUAUUCCCCGCCUUAGACCUGAAACCUGCUACUUUACCGUGGAGCUCCUGUGUUUUUUUAAAUUAGGAAAUAGUAUUUAGAAACCACAAGCUCAGCAUUAAGGGUGUUCAUCAAAACUAGGUUGUCACUAUCCCUCAGGCUUUUCUGUGGGUAGAGGUAGAAAACAACAAUAUUUUUGGACUUAUAAGUAAAUCAUCAGUUUCUACUGUAUUUUUGACAAUAGUUUGGACUGAUUUUUAAAAACCCAUCAGUUUAUACUAUGUUUUUCAAGUCAAAGAUUACAUAGAGUUUUCCUUAACACCUUCACUUUUAUAGAUGCACUUUUUUCUCCUGUGCUGAAAAUUUUAGAUCCUAAAUCACAUUAAUACAAAUAUUUAUUGUUUCAAAAUAAUAAUAACAAUUUUAUUGACAAUAAAAAAAACUUCAGGUUUUUGGGUCUUUUUGUCCUUAUGAUAUUCUACUGGCAACGAACAGACAAAAUAUGUAUUUUGUUUCUCUUUUUCAUAUUUUUAGAAAUCACAUUUUUAUAUUUUUAGAAAUCACAUUUUAAAAUCUUUAUUUCAUCUUAUUUUUUAAUUAUGUGAGAUAUUUACAUGUUUACAAAUUAAAAUUAUAAAAUAAGGUAACUUUAGGGAGGUCUGGAUUCCAUUUCUGCUCUCUUCUUAUUUUCCUUAUCCCUCUAUGGCAUACAAUUUUUAUUUUUUUGAUUCAUUAUUUCAUUGUUUCAUUUUAAAUAUAAGAAGUACUGUAUUUAUCCCUUUAUGAGACAAAAAGUAGCGUAGUAUAGGCUGUUUAAACUUUGUUGGCUUUGUUGCUUAUUUUUACUAAAUAUACUGGACAUAUCUCCACAGUGAUACAUAGAGGUCUUCCUAAUUUCUUUUUCAUAAUUACAUCACUUUUCAUUCUAAUGGAUGUCCAUGGAUUAUUCAACUUUUAAUGAAUAUUUGGGUUGUUUGUAAUCUUUUGUUGUUACAAAUAGUACUGCAAUGGAUGCUCCCUCAUGAAAACGUCAUUUUCUAUUUUAGCUAGUAUAUCUUUGGAAUAGACUCCUAGAAGUGGAAUUGCUUGCUGAAAACAUACAUACACACAUAAUUUUGCUAGAUAUUACUGAAUUCUGUCCCCUGGUGUUUUACCUACCAUUUUUAUAAUCACACCAACAAUGUAUGAGACUGUUUGCUUCUCCAAAGCCUUACCAUCGCUGUACAUUGUAAAGCUUUUGGAUUUUUCCUACAUAACAGGUCAGAGAACUAUUAUACAAAUAUAUUUUAAUAUGCUUUUAUCUAAUAAGUGAGGUUCAACAUCGUUCAUAUGUUUAAAGGCCAUAAGCAUUUCUUUUUCUGCUAAAUAUUUUUUUAAUUAUACUUUAAG